AAGUGCUACGCGGAGGAUUAGAGCAGGCGGUGCGCUGGGGGCGGGAGCAGCGCGGAGCCCGGCUCGGCCACACCGAUCGCCCGCCGCCAUGGGCUCCUCGCAAAGCGUCGAGAUCCCGGGCGGGGGCACCGAGGGCUACCACGUUCUGCGGGUACAAGAAAAUUCCCCAGGACACAGAGCUGGUUUGGAGCCUUUCUUUGAUUUUAUUGUUUCUAUUAAUGGUUCAAGAUUAAAUAAAGACAAUGACACUCUUAAGGAUCUGCUGAAAGCAAACGUUGAAAAGCCUGUAAAGAUGCUUAUCUAUAGCAGCAAAACAUUGGAACUGCGAGAGACCUCAGUCACACCAAGUAACCUGUGGGGCGGCCAGGGCUUAUUGGGAGUGAGCAUUCGUUUCUGCAGCUUUGAUGGGGCAAAUGAAAAUGUUUGGCAUGUGCUGGAGGUGGAAUCAAAUUCUCCUGCAGCACUGGCAGGUCUUAGACCACACAGUGAUUAUAUAAUUGGAGCAGAUACAGUCAUGAAUGAGUCUGAAGAUCUAUUCAGCCUUAUCGAAACACAUGAAGCAAAACCAUUGAAACUGUAUGUGUACAACACAGACACUGAUAACUGUCGAGAAGUGAUUAUUACACCAAAUUCUGCAUGGGGUGGAGAAGGCAGCCUAGGAUGUGGCAUUGGAUAUGGUUAUUUGCAUCGAAUACCUACACGCCCAUUUGAGGAAGGAAAGAAAAUUUCUCUUCCAGGACAAAUGGCUGGUACACCUAUUACACCUCUUAAAGAUGGGUUUACAGAGGUCCAGCUGUCCUCAGUUAAUCCCCCGUCUUUGUCACCACCAGGAACUACAGGAAUUGAACAGAGUCUGACUGGACUUUCUAUUAGCUCAACUCCACCAGCUGUCAGUAGUGUUCUCAGUACAGGUGUACCAACAGUACCGUUAUUGCCACCACAAGUAAACCAGUCCCUCACUUCUGUGCCACCAAUGAAUCCAGCUACUACAUUACCAGGUCUGAUGCCUUUACCAGCAGGACUGCCCAACCUCCCCAACCUCAACCUCAACCUCCCAGCACCACACAUCAUGCCAGGGGUUGGCUUACCAGAACUUGUAAACCCAGGUCUGCCACCUCUUCCUUCCAUGCCUCCCCGAAACUUACCUGGCAUUGCACCUCUCCCCCUGCCAUCCGAGUUCCUCCCGUCAUUCCCCUUGGUUCCAGAGAGCUCUUCUGCAGCAAGCUCAGGAGAGCUGCUGUCUUCCCUCCCGCCCACCAGCAACGCACCCUCCGACCCUGCCACAACUACUGCAAAGGCAGACGCUGCCUCCUCACUCACUGUGGAUGUGACGCCCCCCACUGCCAAGGCCCCCACCACCGUUGAGGACAGAGUCGGCGACUCCACCCCAGUCAGCGAGAAGCCUGUUUCUGCGGCUGUGGAUGCCAAUGCUUCUGAGUCACCUUAACUUUGAACCAUUCUUUGGAAUUGGCGUGGUAUAUUUAACCACGGGAGCGUGUCUGGAAACGCAAACUAUCAUUAAUUUCAUACUAGUUUGUACCGUAUCUGUAGGCAUCCUGUAAAUAAUUCCAAGGGGAAAACUAAACGAGGACGUGGGUUGUAUCCUGCCAGGUUGAGUGGGGCUCACACGCUAGGGUGAGAUGUCAGAAAGCGCUUGUAUUUUAAACAACCAAAAAGAAUUGUAAGGGUGGCUUGCUGCCAGGCUUGCACUGCCGUUCCUGGGGGUGUGCAUCUUCGGGAAAGGUGGUGGCGGGGCGUCCACUAGGUUUCCUGUCCCCUGCUGCUCCUUCCGUAAGAAAAUGAAAUAUUCUAUGCCUAAUACUCACACGCAACAUUUCUUGUACUUUGUAAGUCGUUUGCGAGAAUGCAGACCACCUCACUAAACUGUAAACGGUAAAGAGAUUUUUACUUUUGGUCUCCGUGAGUCGCAUCUCUACUAAGGUUUACACAGGAAUUCCACCUGAAGACUUGUGUUAAAGUUCUACAGCGCGCACUGUUAACUGAACGUCUUUUUCUUCAGCCUAUACGCGGAUCCUUGUUUUGAGCUCUCAGAAUCACUCAGACAACAUUUUGUAACUGCUGCUGUUGCUUUCUACAUACACCUUAUAAAGUGACAUUUCAAAAGAAAUAAGGUGCCACAGUUUUAAACCAGAAGGUGGCACUCUGUGGCUCCUUGUAGUAUUAUAGCUAUACUGGGAAAGCAUAGAUACAGCAAUAAAGUACAGUAAUUUUACUUUUUUUCUUGUGUUACAUCUAAAUUACAACCCUUAAUUGCCACGUGUGCACUUACUACUCUCCAGUAUGUCUUAUUACUCUCCAGUAUGUCACGCAUCUUUAACUUUUCACGUCCUAUGUUUGCUUUCUCCCAUUUUUAAGAGAUGGUAAGUUAACUGGAAUUGAUUUACUGAAUGAAAUUAAAUGCAGAUAUCCCUGUUUUUGAAAUAAGA